GCAGUCCCGGAAGCGGCGAGGGGAAACUGCUCCGCGCGCGCCGCGGGAGGAGGAACCGCCCGGUCCUUUAGGGUCCGGGCCCGGCCGGGCCAUGGAUUCAAUGCCUGAGCCCGCGUCCCGCUGUCUUCUGCUUCUUCCCUUGCUGCUGCUGCUGCUGCUGCUGCUGCCGGCCCCGGAGCUGGGCCCGAGCCAGGCCGGAGCUGAGGAGAACGACUGGGUUCGCCUGCCCAGCAAAUGCGAAGGGUGGACUCCAUUAUGCUGGUGGAAGAGGGCUUCAGUGUGACGAGUGUGGAUGCCAGUGACAAGAUGCUGAAGUAUGCACUUAAGGAGCGCUGGAACCGGCGGCACGAGCCCGCCUUCGACAAGUGGGUCAUCGAAGAAGCCAACUGGAUGACUCUGGACAAAGAUGUGCCCCAGUCAGCAGAGGGUGGCUUUGAUGCUGUCAUCUGCCUUGGAAACAGUUUCGCUCACUUGCCAGACUGCAAAGGGGACCAGAGUGAGCACCGGCUGGCGCUGAAAAACAUUGCGAGCAUGGUGCGGGCAGGGGGCCUACUGGUCAUUGAUCAUCGCAACUACGACCACAUCCUCAGUACAGGCUGUGCACCCCCAGGGAAGAACAUCUACUAUAAGAGUGACUUGACCAAGGACGUCACAACAUCAGUGCUGAUAGUGAACAACAAGGCCCACAUGGUGACCCUGGACUAUACGGUGCAGGUGCCGGGGGCUGGCCAGGAUGGCUCUCCUGGCUUGAGUAAGUUCCGGCUCUCCUACUACCCACACUGUCUGGCAUCCUUCACGGAGCUGCUCCAAGCAGCCUUCGGAGGUAAGUGCCAGCACAGCGUCCUGGGCGACUUCAAGCCUUACAAGCCAGGCCAAACCUACAUUCCCUGCUACUUCAUCCACGUGCUCAAGAGGACAGACUGAGUGUGGCCUCAGCUCCCACAAGCCUCUGCCCAGGCACUGCUAGGCUCUGUCUGGAAGAUGGGGACCAGCAGCCCCACACCAGGGCCAGCCUCUAGAGCAGACUACAGCUGGGGUGCAGGGAUGUGGGUUCCACAGACGGAAGGGUAAACAAUAUAGUCUUUUUCAGUUCCUGCA